GUGUCCAGGAAUUUAUCCAUUUCUUCUGGAUUUUCUAGUUUAUUUGCAUAGAGGUGUUUAUAGUAUUCUCUGAUGGUAGUUUGUAAUUCUGUGGGAUCGGCGAUGAUAUCCCCUUUAUCAUUUUUUGUUGCAUCUAUUUGAUUCUUCUCUCUUUUCUUCUUUAUUAGUCUUGCUAGCGGUCUCUCUAUUUUGUUGAUCUUUCAAAAAACCAGCUCCUGGAUUCAUUGAUUUUUUUGAAGAGUUUUUCAUGUCUCUGUCUCCCUCAGUUCUGCUCUGAUCUUUGUUGUUUCUUGCCUUCUGCUAGCUUUUGAAUUUGUUUGCUCUUGCUUCUCUAGUUCUUUUAAUUGUGAUGUUAGGGUGUCCAUUUUAGAUCUUUCCUGCUUUCUCUUGUGGAAUUUAGUGCUGUAAAUUUCCCUCUACACACUGCUUUAAAUGUGUCCCAGAAAUUCUGGUACGAUGUGUCUUUGUUCUCAUUGGUUUCAAAGAACAUCUUUAUUUCUGCCUUCAUUUCAUUAUUUACCCAGUAGUCAUUCAGGAGCAGGUUGUUCAAUUUCCAUGUAGUUGUGCAGUUCUGAGUGAGUUUCUUAAUCCUGAGAUUGAUUGCCCUGUGGUCUGAGACACAGUUUGUUGUCAUUUGUGUUCUUUUACAUUUGUUCAGGAGUGUUUCACUUCCAAUUAUGUGGUCAAUUUUAGAAUAAGUGUGAUGUGGUGCUGAGAAAAAGGUAUAUUCUGUUGAUUUGGGAUGGAGAGUUCUGUAGAUGUCUAUUAGGUCUGCUUGGUGCAGAGCUGAAUUCAAGUCCUGGAUAUCCUUGUUAACCUUCUGUCUCGUUGAUCUGGCUAAUAUUGACAGUGGGGUGUUAAAGUCUCCGAUUAUUGGGAGUCUAAGUCUCUUUGUAGAUCUCUAAGGACUUGCUUUAUGAGUCUGGGUGCUUCUGUAUUGGGUGCAUAUAUAUUUAGGAUAGUUAGCUCUUCUUGUUGAAUUGAUCCCUUUACCAUUCAGUAAUGGCCUUCUUUGUCUCUUUUGAUCUUUGUUGGUUUAAAGUCUGUUUUAUCAGAGACUAUGAUUGCAACCCCUGCUUUUUUUUGCUUUCCAUUUGCUUGGUAGAUCUUCCUCCAUCCCUUUUUUUUGAGUCUAUGUGUGUCUCUGCACAUGAGAUGGGUCUCCUGAAUGCAGCACACCAAUGGGUCUUGACUCUUUAUCCAGUUUGCCAGUCUGUGUCUUUUAACUGGGGGCAUUUAGCCCAUUUACAUUUAAGGUUAAUAUUGUUAUGUGUGAAUUUGAUCCUGUCAUUAUGAUGUUAGCUGGUUAUUUUGCCCGUUAAUUGAUGCAGUUACUUCAUAGCAUUGAUGAUCUGUAUAAUUUGGCAUGUUUUUGCAGUGGCUGGUACCGGUGUUUCUUUCCAUGUUUAGUGCUUCCUUCAGGAGCUCUUGUAAGGCAGGCCUGGUGGAGACAAAAUCUCUCAGCAUUUGCUUGUCUGUAAAGGAUUUUAUUUCUCCUUCGCUUAUGAAGCUUAGUUUGUCUGGAUAUGAAAUUCUGGGUUGAAAAUUCUUUUCUUUAAGAAUGUUGAAUAUUGAACCCCACUCUUUUCUGGUUUGUGGGGUUUCUGCCGAGAGAUCCCCUGUUAGUCUGAUGGGCUUCCCUUCGUGGGUAACCCGACCUUUCUCUCUGGCUGCCCUUAACAUUUUUUCCUUCAUUUCAACCUUGGUGAAUCUGACAAUUAUGUGUCUUGGGGUUCCUCUUCUUGAGGAGUAUCUUUGUGGUGUUCUCUGAAUUUCCUGGAUUUGAAUGUUGGCCUGCCUUGCUAGGUUGUGGAAGUUCUCCUGGAUAAUAUCCUGAAGAGUGUUUUCUAACUUGGUUCCAUUCUCCCCAUCACUUUCAGGUACAACAAUCAAACAUAGAUUUGGUCUUUUCACAUAGUCCCAUAUUUCUUGGAGGCUUUUUUCAUUUCUUUUUACUCUUUUUUCUCUAAUCUUGUCUCCUCGCUCUGUUUUAUUAAUUUAUCUUGAAUCACUGAUAUCCUUUCUUCCACUUGAUUGAAUCGGCUAUUGAAGCUUGUGCAUGCAUCACGAAGUUCUCAUGCUAUGGUUUUCAGCUCCAUCAGGUCAUUUAAGGUCUUCUCUACACUGUUUAUUCUAGUUAGCCAUUCGCCUGACCUUUUUUCAAGGUUUUUUGCUUUCUUGCAUUGGGUUAGAACAUGCUCCUUUAGCUCGGAGAAGUUUGAUUACUGACCUUUUGAAGCCUACUUCUGUCAACUCGUCAAACUCGUUCUCCAUCCAGUUUUGUUCCAUUGCUGGCAAGGAUCUGCUAUCCUUUGGAGGAGAAGAGGCAGUCUGGUUUUUGGAAUUUUCAGCUUUUGUGUUCUGGUUUCUCCCCAUUUUUGUGGUUUUAUUUACCUUUGGUCUUUGAUGUUGGUGACCUACAGAUGGGGUUUUGGUGUGGAUGUCCUUUUUGUUGAUGUUGAUGCUAUUCCUUUCUGUUUAUUAGUUUUCCUUCUAACAGUCAGGCCUCUCAACUGUAGGUCUGUUGGAGUUUGCUAGAGGUCCACUUCAGAACCUAUUUGCCUGGGUAUCACCAGGGGAGGCUGCAGAACAGCAAAUAUUGCUGCUUGGUCCUUCCUCUGGAUGCUUCGUCCCAGAGGGGCACCCGCCUGUAUGAGGUGUCUGUCGGCCCCUACUGGGAGGUGUCUCCCAGUCAGGCUACACGGGUCAGGGACCCACUUGAGGAGGCAGUCUGUCCGUUCUCAGAGCUCAAACUCCGUGCUGGGAGAAUCACUGCUCUCUUCCGAGCUGUUAGACAGGGACAUUUAAGUCUGCAGAAGUUGUCUGCUGCCUUUUGUUCAGCUAUGCCCUGCCCACAGAGGUGGCGUCUAGCGAGGCGGUAGGCCUUGCUGAGCUGCGGUGGGCUCUGCCCAGUUCGAGCUUCCUGGCUGGUUUGUUUACCUAUUCAAGCCUCAACAAUGGUGGAUGCCCCUCCCCCUGCUGGGCUGCAGUGUUGCAGGUGGAUCUCAGACUGCUGCGCUAGCAUUGAGCAAGGCUCUGUGGGCGUGGGACCCACCAAGCCAGGCACAGGAGGGAAUCUCCUGGUCUGCCAGUUGCUGAGACUGUGGGAAAAGUGCAGUAUUUGGACGAGAGUGUACCAUUCCUCCAGGUACAGUCUGUCACGGCUUCCCUUGCUUAGGAAAGGGAAAUUCCCCAACCCCUUGUGCUUCCCAGGUGAGGCGACACCCUGCCCUGCUUCAGCUCACCCUCCAUGGGCUGCACCCACUGUCCAACCAGUCCCAAUGAGAUGAACCAGGUACCUCAAUUGGAAAUGCAGAAAUCACCUGUCUUCUGCGUCAACCUUGCUAGGUGCUGCAGACUGGAGCUGUUCCUAUUUGGCCAUCUUGGAAGGAACCCAUCUUAUAUCUCCAAAUGGUUAUAUGUAAAGUCAGAUGUGCCACUGAACUUGACAGACACAAAAUUCUACUGCAUUUGGGCUUUAUAAUGGCAAGCCUGCUCUUUUUAGUGGUGAACUUGACUUGCGCAAUGCUAGUUCAUGGAGAUGUCCCAGAAAAUCAGUUGAAGUGGACUGUGUUUGUUCGAGCAUUAAUUAAUGAUAGCCUGUUUAUUCUUUGUGCCAUCUCUUUAGUGUGUUACAUAUGCAAAAUUACAAAAAUGUCAUCAGCUAAUGUCUACCUCGAAUCAAAGGGUAUGUCUCUGUGCCAGACUGUCGUCGUGGGCUCUGUAGUCAUUCUUCUGUACUCUUCCAGAGCUUGUUAUAAUUUGGUGGUGGUCACCAUAUCUCAGGAUACAUUAGAAAGUCCAUUUAAUUAUGGCUGGGAUAAUCUUUCAGAUAAGGCUCAUGUAGAAGACAUAAGUGGAGAAGAGUAUAUAGUAUUUGGAAUGGUCCUCUUUCUGUGGGAACAUGUGCCAGCAUGGUCGGUGGUACUGUUUUUCCGGGCACAGAGAUUAAACCAGAAUUUGGCACCUGCUGGCAUGAUAAAUAGUCACAGUUAUAGUUCCAGAGCUUACUUUUUCGACAAUCCAAGACGAUAUGAUAGUGAUGAUGACCUGCCAAGACUGGGAAGUUCAAGAGAAGGAAGUUUACCAAAUUCGCAAAGUUUGGGCUGGUAUGGCACCAUGACUGGGUGUGGCAGCAGCAGUUACACAGUCACUCCCCACCUGAAUGGACCUAUGACAGAUACUGCUCCUUUGCUCUUUACUUGUAGUAAUUUAGAUUUGAACAAUCAUCAUAGCUUAUAUGUGACACCACAAAACUGACAGCAUCACCAAGUCAUGAUUCUUGAGUUGUUUUUCAUAAAUGUGUAUAUUCAAUGUGUUUAAAUUCCAUCUACAUAAACAUUCCAUUAUCUGUUGCAACUGAAAACAAAAUCUGGAAGUGUGGCUGUGUUUGGUAAAUAACACAGCUAUUAUUUUUGACCUCUUCAUAGUAAAAUGAAGUAAAAUGGAAAGUUUGGAGUAGGAGAAAAGAGAGAUUAGAUCUUAAGGCACUUGAUGGCCUCCAAAAAUCCUGACUUUGGAACAUCAAAUGCAUAUGUGCACUUUUAUCUUUGUUCUGAGUCACUGCAGUCCCCAAAGUCAUAUGCCAAUGUUCACACUGAAAUACUGUAUUGUACACCAAACUGGAAGGCAAUUUUCCUAUGAAAAUCAAAGCCGGUAUAUUCAUUGGUAUGCUCUAUACAGAUAUCUUAAUAAAAAUUUUAUAGUGUGAACAGUGCACAGAGUUAAGGCAUAAAAAUGUAUCAUUCUUUAUAAAAAUCUACUGAAAAUGUGUAAUCAUUGAAGACAGUUCUUUUAAGCAUGAUUUUAAAAUAGCAACUGAAAUUCAAUCAUUUUAAACAAAUGAUGGUAGUAAUCCAUUAGUUAUGGCCAGCAGUGUUCUUUGGAGAGCCACAAUAAUUUCAAGAGGAAAAUAUACCAGUGAAAAUUGUGUGGCUAUUUUGAGUAGAAUUGGUCAGUUGAUUAUUUUGUGUAAUUGAGAUAUAUGUAGUAGUUUAAGCAUGAUUCUUGAAGAAAGCAAUAGUGACUUUUGCAUAGGGAGAUUUUGGUAGAAACUUCUUGGGACUAAACAAGUUUAGAGAUGCAUUUAAGAAUUAUUCACAAAAUGUGUAAUUCUAAAUUAAAACAUAAAUAUAUUUUCAAAAGCAUUUGAUUUCUCUGAAGCAUGAUAUAGCUGGUCUUACCUAGUGAAUCAGGAUUGUCCUCAGGUAAAUGAAAUCAUGAUACAUUAUUGCAGUGAACUCAAGUGCAAUACUUUGUAAGACAUAUAAUUCCUAUGAUUUUCACAUUUUUAUAUCUUAUAUAUGGGAAAAGCCAAAUUAAAUUGAAUUCAGAUUAAUUCCAGCAUUAGACUAAAUGAGCAAACUUAAGUAAAUGUACAAACUAGGUAAGUAUAAAACCACAGGUUAACAAUAUUGGAGUACUUUUAGAAUUACAUUAAAACUGUCUUAAAUGUCCUAUCCCAAAUCUAAAAAAAAAGAAAAUGGCAGGCUGAGAUAAUACAGAAUUUUAAAAUGCACUUUGUACCAGUGUCUAUAUGGAAAGAAGUAGAUGCUGAAUACCUCAAGAUGCCAAGGGAACAAGCAACAUUGGGAAGUUGUCACAACAUGCUCAAAGACAAACUACAAUUGUCUGCUAGCUAUUUCUUCAGAACUGGAACUAAUACGACUAUCCUUUUCUGUUUUAUACUUUGAUUAGAAUGUUAUUUCCUCGCUUACUUAAAAUGUACUUCAACUUUUUAACAACUGAUACAAUAACUUCAUAAAAGUAUAACACUAGGUUGAAACCUUAAGGAAAAAUUGAAAUUGUUAAUGCUUUCGAUCUUUUGGGAGGCCAGUACACAGACAAAUAAAUUUCUUCUUUUUAUGAUACAAAAUGACUUUGUAUUCAAUCAGAAGCAUAUACUUAUGUUAUUUUGGGUUUGUUUAUAAUUCUCUCAUUGUAACCAAAUUAUUUUAAAAUGUAUAGUAUAAAAAGUUACCCGUGGUAUUAAGUGACAAAAGCGUACUUUUAUUACAACUCCAGUUGUUAGAUUGCUUCUCAGAAUGCUAACUGUUUAUUUUGCUAAUAAUGUUAGGCAUCUAAUCAUCUAGAGCUGUCCAAAAAGAUAUGUUGUCUUUGUUAAUCCUUGGGGUUCAAGGUGAUAAAGUUUUUCUAGUAAGGCUCCCCUCGAUAAUGUUCCUAUUUGACCAAACUAACAAAGAUUACUUUUUAAAAAUUUUUCAGAUAAAAUAACUUGGUUCUUUCUGCUGCAUUAGUUGAUUGUUCCAAAUUUGAGGUUUGUAAGUUUAUUCUUAUCACUGACUAGGGUACCCAAAUUCUUGCAUUUGUCUCCUUAUACACAUCUAACAUAUCACCAAAGACAAAUAAAGAUACACUCUGGCCCAAUCUUUGCUUAAAAAUUCCAAAGCACUAGGAGCACUUUAAGUUUGGUCUCGAAAGGAGUUGUUUAUAAAAUCAAAGGGCUACCGAUUCCCUGUUCAUCCUGCACUGAAGCACAUGAUGACAGUAUCAAACCUUCAUUUUUGUUCAUUAAAAAGUGAAUUUCAUUACUUAAGUGUGUAAUUCUAUAGUGAUUAGCAGUAUUUGUUUUCAUCAUUUCACUUGGGUGGCCAUUAAUUUUGAAACCUUUACCACUCAUUGUAGUUGGUUGUAGUUUUAUGGAAAAUGUAAUUUAUAGCUAAAGUGGCUUUUUUAUGCAUAGCUGCCUUUUUUAUUGUUUAACAGUGUUUCUCAGCUAUAUAAUCAGUUUCAAACUGGUUGUAAAAGUAUAGCUGUGGCCAAUGAAUGUAUUUAUUUGUUGUUUCACUAAAUUGUAACAAAACACUACUAUUAAAAAUAAAAGUGUUUGUGCUUUUA